GACUCAGCAUCCUCGGUGGGCUCGCCUCCUCCCCCGGAACAGCUGUCUAAAAUCCAUGGGCGUGGAAACGCCACGCCACGCCCCGCUCCCGACUUCUUCAGCUCAGGCCCCAGAACUGACCACCCCACCAGUCCUCUGCCCCAGUCCCUCUGCCUUCACUCCCAUGGCCACCUGUGCUCCAGGGCCUGCCUGACCCCUGUCCAGCGGCCCUGAAGUAAGGUCUGUGAUGUCUAAAUGCCGAUACCUCAGUUUCCCCAUCUUUAGAACGGGGCUCUUGUUUGGAACUGUGCCCGCCACAGCCUGCACGCCUAGAACACUGCCUGUAACGUGGAAGGUGUUCGAUCUAUAGAGUUUUGUCGAAUGAAUGAAUGAAGCCGACUAGUGCACAGGGAGUGCAGCGGCGCGAUGGUAGCUCUCUGCAGCCUCCAACACCUGGGCUCCAGUGAUCCCCGGGCUCUGCCCACCCUCCCCACUGCCACUUCCGGGCAGAGGCCAGCAAAGCGGCGGCGCAAGAGUCCCGCCAUGGCCGCUCUCACCCGGGACCCCCAGUUCCAGAAGCUGCAGCAAUGGUACCGCGAGCACCGCUCCGAGCUGAACCUGCGCCGCCUCUUCGAUGCCAACAAGGACCGCUUCAACCACUUCAGCUUGACCCUCAACACCAACCAUGGGCAUAUCCUGGUGGAUUACUCCAAGAACCUGGUGACGGAGGACGUGAUGCGGAUGCUGGUGGACUUGGCCAAGUCCAGGGGCGUGGAGGCCGCCCGGGAGCGGAUGUUCAAUGGUGAGAAGAUCAACUACACCGAGGGUCGAGCCGUGCUGCACGUGGCUCUGCGGAACCGGUCAAACACACCCAUCCUGGUAGACGGCAAGGAUGUGAUGCCAGAGGUCAACAAGGUUCUGGACAAGAUGAAGUCUUUCUGCCAGCGUGUCCGGAGCGGUGACUGGAAGGGGUACACAGGCAAGACCAUCACGGACGUCAUCAACAUUGGCAUUGGCGGCUCCGACCUGGGGCCCCUCAUGGUGACUGAAGCCCUUAAGCCAUACUCUUCAGGAGGUCCCCGCGUCUGGUAUGUCUCCAACAUUGAUGGAACUCACAUUGCCAAAACCCUGGCCCAGCUGAACCCCGAGUCCUCCCUGUUCAUCAUUGCCUCCAAGACCUUUACUACCCAGGAGACCAUCACGAAUGCAGAGACGGCGAAGGAGUGGUUUCUCCAGGCGGCCAAGGAUCCUUCUGCAGUGGCGAAGCACUUUGUUGCCCUGUCUACUAACACAACCAAAGUGAAGGAGUUUGGAAUUGACCCUCAAAACAUGUUCGAGUUCUGGGAUUGGGUGGGAGGACGCUACUCGCUGUGGUCGGCCAUCGGACUCUCCAUUGCCCUGCACGUGGGUUUUGACAACUUCGAGCAGCUGCUCUCGGGGGCUCACUGGAUGGACCAGCACUUCCGCACGACGCCCCUGGAGAAGAACGCCCCCGUCUUGCUGGCCCUGCUGGGUAUCUGGUACAUCAACUGCUUUGGGUGUGAGACACACGCCAUGCUGCCCUAUGACCAGUACCUGCACCGCUUUGCUGCGUACUUCCAGCAGGGCGACAUGGAGUCCAAUGGGAAAUACAUCACCAAAUCUGGAACCCGUGUGGACCACCAGACAGGCCCCAUUGUGUGGGGGGAGCCAGGGACCAAUGGCCAGCAUGCUUUUUACCAGCUCAUCCACCAAGGCACCAAGAUGAUACCCUGUGACUUCCUCAUCCCGGUCCAGACCCAGCACCCCAUACGGAAGGGUCUGCAUCACAAGAUCCUCCUGGCCAACUUCUUGGCCCAGACAGAGGCCCUGAUGAGGGGAAAAUCGACGGAGGAGGCCCGAAAGGAGCUCCAGGCUGCGGGCAAGAGUCCAGAGGACCUUGAGAGGCUGCUGCCACAUAAGGUCUUUGAAGGAAAUCGCCCAACCAACUCUAUUGUGUUCACCAAGCUCACACCAUUCAUGCUUGGAGCCUUGGUCGCCAUGUAUGAGCACAAGAUCUUCGUUCAGGGCAUCAUCUGGGACAUCAACAGCUUUGACCAGUGGGGAGUGGAGCUGGGAAAGCAGCUGGCUAAGAAAAUAGAGCCUGAGCUUGAUGGCAGUGCUCAAGUGACCUCUCACGACGCUUCUACCAAUGGGCUCAUCAACUUCAUCAAGCAGCAGCGCGAGGCCAGAGUCCAAUAAACUCGUGCUCAUCUGCAGCCUCCUCUGUGACUCCCCUUUCUCUUCUCGUCCCUCCUCCCCGGAGCCGGCACUGCAUGUUCCUGGACACCACCCAGAGCACCCUCUGGUUGUGGGCUUGGACCACGAGCCCUUAGCAGGGAAGGCUGGUCUCCCCCAGCCUAACCCCCAGCCCCUCCAUGUCUAUGCUCCCUCUGUGUUAGAAUUGGCUGAAGUGUUUUUGUGCAGCUGACUUUUCUGACCCAUGUUCACGUUGUUCACAUCCCAUGUAGAAAAAUAAAGAUGCCACGGAGGAGGUUGUAGGCUCAGCCUCUGAUUUUUUUUUUCCUGUGAUGGUGCUUUAUGUAGCAGAGGGCAGGAGCGCUCAGCAGGACGCAGGCUGUGCCUCUGCGGACACUUAACACUAAGUGGUGAGCGGGUCUAGAGUGGAGCAAGGUGCCCUGAGAAGACAAUAGUGGGGUGGGGGCACAAUCAGUCAGGACGGCAACUUGGCCUGUGUCACCAAAUCCCAAGACUGUUUUCCACUCCUCACCUCUGUGACUGGAGAAAUUGGAUACUCUGUUCACUCGAUGGUUCUAAAAACUGCAUUGAGAUUAUGUUUGUUUCGGGUGAAUUCCUGGACAAGACCGAGGAUGACUGCCAUCUCCUGGCAAGACGCUCAGGUAGUUCUUUUGCUUUAAAAGGCAGAUAUUGAAAACUGGAAUUUUUUUUUUUUGAGUCUCGCUCUGUCACCCAGACUGGAGUGCAGUGGUGCAAUCUCGGCUCACUGCAACCUCCGCCUCCCGGGUUCAAGCUAUUCUCCUGCCUCAGCCUCCCGAGUAGCUGGGAUUACACGGCGCACACCACCAUACCCAGCUAAUUUUUGUAUUUUUAGUAGUGAAGGGGUUUUACCAUGUUGGGCAGGCUGGUCUUGAACUCCUGACCUCAGGUGAUCUGCCCGCCUCAGCCUCCCACAGUGCUGGGAUUACAGGUAUGAGCCACCACGCCCGGCCCAUUUUUUUUUUUUUUUUGACAACUUUUUUUUUUUUUUGAGACAGGGUCUUGUUCCAUUGCCCAGACUGGAGUGCAGUGGCAUGAUCACAGCUCACUGCAGCCAGUAAUCCUCUUGCCUCAGCCUCCCAAGUAGUUGAGACUACAGGUUGUACCACUAUGCCCUGCUAGUUUUUUCAUUUUUUGUAGAGAGACGGGUCUUUUUUUUUUUUGAGACGGAGUCUCGCUCUGUCGCCCAAGCUGGAGUGCAGUAGCACGGUCUCAGCUCAUUGCAAGCUCCGCCUCCCAGGUUCACGCCAUUCUCCUGCCUCAGACUCCUGUGUAGCUGGGAGUACAGGCACCUGCCACCAUGCCCAGCUAAUUUUUUAUAUAUUUUUUUAGCAGAGACAGUGUCUCACUGUGUUAGUCAGGAUGGUCUCGAUCUCCUGACCUCGUGAUCCGCCCGCCUCAGCCUCCCAAAGUGCUGGGAUUACAGGCGUGAGCCACCGCGCCCAGCAAGGCGGGUCUUGCUGUGUUUCCCAGACUAGACUGGUCUUGAAUUCCAGGGCUCAAGAGAUCUCCCACCUCAGCCUCCCACAGUGCUGGGAUUACAGGCGUGAGCCGCCACACCCAGCCUAUUCAAAAUUUUUUUUUCUUAGAGACAGGGUCUUUGUUGCCCAGGCUGGACUGCAGUGAUACAAUCAUAGCUGACUGAAGCCUCAAAUUCCCAGGCUAAGGUGAUCUUCUCACCUCAGCCUUCCAAGUAGCUGGGUCCGCAGAUGCAUGCCAGUACACCCAGCUCAUUUAAAAAAAAAUUUUUUUCUUUUUUGAGAGUCUUGCUUUGUUGCCCAGGCUGGAGUGCAGUGGUGUGAUCUCGGCUCACUGCAAGCUCCACCUCCCGGCUUCACGCCAUUCUCCUGCCUCAGCCUCCCGAGUAGCUGGGACUACAGGUGCCCGCCACCACACCCGGCUAAUUUUUUGUAUUUUUAGUAGAGACGGGGUUUCACCGUGUUAGCCAGGAUGGUCUUGAUCUCCUGACCUCAUGAUCCGCCUGCUUUGGCCUCCCAAAGUGCUGGGAUUACAGGCGUGAGUCACCGCGCCCGGCUCAUUUUAAAAUUUUUGUAGAUCAGUGUACUGUUGUAAAAAAAAAAAAAUAAGAAAAAUAAAAAAUAAAUUUUUGUAGUGAUAGGAUCCCACUGAGGCCAGAGAAUAGGGUCUGGAGACAAAGGAGCAUUCACUUCAGCCUCUGACUGGUGGCAGGCCAAGUCUUUAUUUACAUAGGGUGUAACCAAAUAGGAAACCUCUAAAGGGUACUUAAACCCCAGAUUUUCUACACAGGGCACUUGCUUGAGCCUCAUCCCGCUUUCUGGAAUGUACUUUUGCUUCAAUAAAUCUGUGCUUUUGUUCCUUC